AUUGGGACGCUGCGGCCUGGCCUUCAGGCCACUGGCUACCGAACCCCGGGGCUCUUCACCAGUCCAGCUCGUUUCCAGCACCAUGUCGGUGCGGACGCUACCGCUGCUCUUCUUGAACUUGGGCGGGGAGAUGCUUUACAUCCUCGACCAACGGCUGCGGGCCCAGAACAUCCCGGGAGACAAGGCCCGCAAAGAUUUUGACUGAGUGUCAAACACUAUGUGAGAUACUAUAUGGAGCCUGAUGCAGCCCUUCUGGACAUUCACUGGAGAUGAAUGGACAGAGGUGGACAGAAAACGAGUUCUGAAUGACAUCAUCUCCACCAUGUUCAAUAGAAAGUUUAUGGAGGAAUUAUUCAAGCCUCAAGAGCUCUACUCCAAGAAGGCCCUGAGGACUGUCUAUGAGCGCCUGGCUCAUGCCUCCAUUAUGAAACUGAACCAGGCCAGCAUGGAUAAGCUCUAUGACCUGAUGACCAUGGCUUUCAAAUAUCAAGUAUUGCUGUGUCCCCGACCCAAGGAUGUGCUGCUGGUCACUUUCAAUCACUUGGAUACCAUCAAGGGAUUCAUCCGAGACUCCCCAACCAUCCUGCAGCAAGUGGACGAGACUUUGCGGCAGCUGACAGAAAUAUAUGGUGGUCUCUCUGCAGGGGAGUUCCAGCUGAUCCGGCAGACACUCCUCAUCUUCUUCCAAGACCUGCACAUCCGAGUAUCCAUGUUUCUAAAGGACAAAGUUCAGAAUAAUAACGGUCGCUUUGUGUUGCCGGUGUCCGGGCCUGUUCCUUGGGGAACUGAAGUUCCAGGACUCAUCAGAAUGUUCAACAACAAAGGUGAAGAAGUGAAGAGGAUAGAAUUCAAGCAUGGUGGAAACUAUGUCCCUGCACCCAAAGAAGGUUCUUUUGAACUUUAUGGAGACCGAGUCCUGAAACUGGGAACUAACAUGUACAGCGUGAAUCAGCCUGUGGAAACUCAUGUGUCUGGAUCAUCAAAGAACUUAGCCUCAUGGACCCAGGAAAGCAUUGCUCCAAACCCUCUUGCUAAAGAAGAGCUGAAUUUCUUGGCCAGGCUGAUGGGAGGGAUGGAGAUUAAGAAACCCAGUGGCCCUGAGCCCGGAUUCCGGUUGAAUCUCUUUACCACCGAUGAAGAAGAGGAACAAGCAGCGCUAACCAGGCCAGAAGAGUUAUCCUAUGAAGUUAUCAACAUACAAGCCACCCAGGACCAGCAACGGAGCGAGGAGCUGGCUCGAAUCAUGGGGGAGUUUGAGAUCACGGAGCAGCCAAGGCUGAGCACCAGCAAAGGGGACGAUUUGCUCGCCAUGAUGGAUGAGUUAUAGCUGUUCUGACCAGGCGUCCUCUGCCCCCAGGGAGAGGCUGCUGGAUGGUGACCCCUGGGGAAUGCCCCAUGGCCCAGAAUGAUGCUGCUAGUUUUCUACUGAGUGAAGCCAUUACGUCUAUUUCUUAUUUAUGUUGUAAGGAACUGUGUGAGUCUCCCUUGAGGAGCACUCACUCUUGAAGGCACACACAUACACAUAUUUUCAGUGAAAUAUAUUCUGACUUUUAAACUUGA